CCUCCCCCUUUCAGAACACUCAAUGUCGGAACGUUCCGAAGAUGACGUCGGAGCGUUCUCGAAUCCCGUGUCUCUCGGCUGCUGCUGCCGAAGGAACAGGGAAAAAGCAACAAGAAGGAAGAGCAAUGGCGACACUGGAUCGCAAAGUGCCCAGUCCGGAGGCGUUUCUGGGCAAACCCUGGUCCUCCUGGAUCGACGCCGCCAAAUUACACUGCUCCGACAAUGUAGAUUUAGAAGAGGCUGGAAAAGAGGGUGGAAAAAGCAGGGAGGUUAUGAGGCUUAAUAAAGAAGAUAUGCACUUAUUUGGCCAUUACCCAGCACAUGACGACUUCUAUCUCGUAGUGUGCAGUGCCUGUAACCAGGUCGUCAAGCCACAGGUUUUCCAGUCGCACUGCGAGAGAAGACACGGUUCAAUGUGUAGACCUUCUCCCUCUCCAGUGUCUCCAGCCUCCAAUCCCAGGACAUCACUAGUACAGGUGAAAACAAAAGCCUGUCUCAGCGGCCAUCACUCUGCCAGCAGCACCUCAAAGCCAUUCAAAACGCCCAAAGACAAUCUACUUACCUCCAGCAGCAAACAGCACACAGUCUUUCCUGCGAAAGGAUCAAGGGAUAAACCAUGUGUUCCAGUUCCUGUAGUCAGUUUAGAGAAAAUUCCUAACCUAGUGAAGGCAGAUGGUGCCAAUGUCAAAAUGAACUCCACAACCACUACUGCAGUUUCUGCCUCCUCCACCUCGUCCUCUGCCGUCUCCACCCCUCCUUUAAUUAAGCCUGUCCUGAUGUCCAAGUCAGUGCCACCUUCACCAGAGAAGAUCUUAAAUGGCAAAGGAAUUCUGCCAACCACCAUAGACAAGAAACACCAAAAUGGCACCAAAAACAGCAACAAGCCUUACAGGAGACUUUCAGAGAGAGAAUUUGACCCAAAUAAACACUGUGGAGUAUUGGAUCCCGAGACAAAGAAACCUUGCACAAGAUCCCUCACCUGCAAGACACAUUCGCUAAGCCAUCGGAGGGCAGUCCCAGGCCGGAAAAAGCAAUUUGACCUCCUCCUGGCAGAACACAAAGCAAAGUCCCGGGAAAAAGAAGUUAAAGAUAAAGAGCAUCUCCUGACUUCCACGAGGGAAAUACUUCCAAGCCAAUCCGGGCCGGCACAGGAUUCUCUGCUAGGGUCUUCAGGGAGCUCUGGGCCAGAACCAAAAGUUGCAUCCCCUGCAAAAUCCAGACCACCCAACUCUGUACUUCCUAGACCAUCAUCUGCAAAUAGCAUAAGCAGCAGCACAUCUUCAAAUCAUAGCGGCCACACUCCAGAGCCCCCACUCCCACCGGUUGGAGGUGACCUCGCCAGCCGACUGUCCAGUGAUGAAGGGGAGAUGGACGGAGCCGACGAAUCCGAGAAGCUAGACUGUCAGUUCUCCACGCACCACCCCAGACCUCUGGCGUUUUGCUCAUUUGGGAGUCGCCUCAUGGGACGAGGGUACUAUGUGUUUGAUAGAAGAUGGGAUCGUUUUCGAUUCGCACUAAACUCCAUGGUAGAAAAACACCUGAAUUCACAGAUGUGGAAGAAGAUCCCUCCUGCGGCAGAUAGCCCCCUGCCCUCGCCAGCAGCCCACAUCACCACCCCCGUUCCAGCAUCCGUUUUGCAGCCUUUCAGCAACCCCAGUGCUGUGUAUCUUCCUUCAGCUCCCAUCAGCUCGAGGCUCACCUCUUCUUACAUAAUGACAUCAGCCAUGCUCUCAAACGCAGCUUUCGUGACAUCGCCGGACCCGAGCGCCCUCAUGUCCCACACCACAGCUUUCCCUCAUGUGGCCGCAACCCUCAGCAUCAUGGACUCAACCUUCAAGGCCCCAUCCGCCGUGUCCCCGAUACCAGCCGUCAUCCCUUCCCCAUCCCACAAGCCAUCCAAAACCAAAACCAGCAAAUCCUCAAAAGUCAAAGACCUGUCCACCCGUAGCGACGAGUCUCCAAGUAACAAAAAAAGGAAGCCACAGUCUUCGACUUCCUCCUCCUCCUCCUCCUCCUCCUCUUCCUUGCAGACAUCCCUCUCGUCUCCACUGUCAGGGCCUCACAAAAAGAACUGUGUUUUGAAUGCCAGUUCUGCUUUGAACUCCUAUCAGGCGGCCCCUCCCUAUAACAGCCUGUCUGUGCACAACUCAAACAAUGGGGUGAGCCCACUCAGUGCCAAACUGGAGCCCUCAGGACGGACCUCGCUGCCCGGCGGCCCCGCGGACAUAGUGAGACAGGUGGGCGCGGUGGGAGGCAGCAGUGACUCCUGUCCCCUCUCUGUGCCCUCCCUUGCGCUCCACGCAGGGGACCUCUCUCUGGCCUCACACAAUGCUGUGUCUUCUCUGCCCCUCUCUUUUGACAAAUCAGAAGGAAAAAAGCGUAAGAACUCGAGUUCUAGUAGCAAAGCCUGUAAAAUCACUAAAAUGCCUGGUAUGAAUAGCGUUCACAAAAAGAACCCGCCCAGCCUUCUCGCACCGGUGCCCGAUCCCGUUAACAGCACCUCCUCUCGGCAGGUUGGGAAAAAUAGCAGCCUAGCUUUGUCACAAUCCAGUCCUUCAAGUAUAUCCAGCCCAGGACACAGCCGACAGAAGAACACAAACAGAACGGGCAGGAUAAGGACUCUUCCAUAACAAGACUAUGAAGCCACUUCCACAUCAAUUCCAGGCCACCUAAUCCCAUCCGAGGAGGCCAUGGGGAGGAGGAGGGAGGGGAGUGGGCUGGGGGGAGAGUCUGUUUUCUGUGCACUCCCUGUGACUCUGGCCUUUCUUCUUCUUUUUUUAAUUGACCAAUUUUUAGUUAAAAAGGCAAAAGAAGGUGAAUUUGAGAUUUACAGAAAACAGUUCCAGUGUUUGGUUUCCGCUGUCUUUCCUUUCAUUUGCCAUGUUUUUACAUUCUUCCAAAUUUGGGGUCACUCCCCUAGCUCCUGAUGCUGCUACUGUACCAUCCUUUUGCUCCAGCCAUGAGAGCAGACAUUGCAGAAUGUUGGUUCCAGGUUGGCAUGCUCUGAAGCUCUUGAACUGUAGCACAGGCAGAGCCCUUUUUCUUCCUGUCAUCUCCACCCGAUUCCUUCCAUCCCUACGUCUACCACUCUCUGGGUCCUCACUGGUCUUCAAAGGACCUGGCUCUCAUAGGAUCCCCUCAGGAUUGUGUGCAGGGAGAGGGGGCUUUGCUGGGGAGGAGCUGGGAGUGGAGAGUUGGAGGGUGGGUGGGGUUCCCUCAUCCAGUUUCCACAGCCCACCAUGGCUGGAGCCAAAUGCUAGAAGCGAGAUUGAGAACAGUGGCCGUUUAGUGAUGUGGUUUACCUAAUACCACUGUCCAGCUGUGCAGCUCAGAAAGGAUAAACCAGUCAGGGACAGGGGCCAGAACAGGUUUGGGAAGGUGGCAGCAAGCAGAGCAUGGUGGGUAGGAGAUGAUCCCUAAAAAAACUGGAGACUGUGGUGGUCUGAGCUGGUCAGGAAUCUGCAGAAUCCCUUCCAGGAAUCAGUGUGCCAGUGCCCACAGCAGGGUGAGCUAGGAGGGAGAAAUCCCAGGAAAAAGGUCGUGAGAACCCAGAAAGCCACUCCAUGAGGAGGCACGGUGACCACAGCUGCUAAAGGUUCUUAGGCUGCCUUCCUGGGCUAGGAAGAGCCCCCCAGGGAGAGCUUCCACAAAAGGGUAUGUGUCAAACCUUUUGUCAGAAUAAAUAAUAGCAUUUCCCACCCACCCCCAUGCCCUGGGCCACAGGGACUUGGUGGGAUCAGCACACCCAUGGAUCAGCUUUUGCUGUCUUAGAGACAGCCAUCCCCAUGAAGGAAUGGUAAGGACAGCCACUGCUCAGUGAAGAACAGCCAUUUGGAAGAGCCACGCUGGAGCCCUGCAGCCAUAGAACUAUUCACACUGGAGUUUUAAAAGAAACAGCAAUACCAUAAGCUCUAGUAGGGAAUCAUAAUCAGGAAAGGAAUUCACAACAUAAAAUAGGUGUUCUGUGCUAUUAAUCAUGUAACUUUGUAUAUGAUGUAUAGCAAAGAUACUGGGAGGUUUUGUUUCAUCCUUAAAUCAGAAAUGAAUGCUAGUUUCAUAGCUGGGCAGAACCCUCAUCCCCACCCCAAAGUUUUCCUUUUCUUUCCCGUUCCCCCAACCCAAAGAUCAGACUACUGUUAAGUUUCACCACACAAUUGGAAUUGCAAAGACGGGAGGCAAAUGGAGUGAUUUUCAUCAAUGGAAUUGCACUGACAGUGAGUGUUUCUUAUAGGAUUACUAAAUUUUUUAAUAUAAAAUGAUUUGUUUAAAAAUCAGGAGUUGAUAUUAAGUACCAGGACAUUAGUUCGGAUGAUUUCAUUUUUAUUUCUACAGUGUUAAAAGUGCACUUAUAUGCUGGUUUAUUUACGUCUUGGGAAAAGAGACUGCAAAUUGAAGGGAUGAUUGUUACUUUUUCUUUUUUUAAAAAAAAAAGGUUAAGGAGAUUUUAAGACUUAUAAAUGUUUAAGAAAUUAUAAACAAGGUUAGACCCUUUGAAAAAAAGUUUAGAAGAUAUUCUUAAAGUAAAUUUUUAUAGUGUUAAUUUUGUAAUAAUUUAUGUUUUACUAUAUUACAGAGCUAACUGACCAGAAUAGUUUCAGAAACAAUAUGAAACUUAGGAAAGUUUAAGCAAUGUUUAUAUUUUUAAAAUGUUCUUUGAAUUAUGUUUUUAUUGUACAUUUCUUCAGACUGAAAAGUAUGUACAUAUCUUUGUUAUUUUUGCACAAUUUUGUCUUGUUCGGUUUCAGAGGUCUGUUGUUUUUUAUAAUUUAUUUUGAGUUGUAAAACUUGCAGGAGUAAAAACAAAAAACAAAAUCUCCACAACAAAAUAACCCUCUGAUUUAUAAACUCUUAUAGUCAAAGAGGGAAAACAAAGGUUGAGAGAUUAAGUGGCUGCUUCUGAGAAAUAAUGUCUCAAGGACUAAAGGAGCAAUUCAAUAGGUUUAGACAUUGUAGCUCUCUACAUCUUGAAUUGGAAGCUGGAAUAAAGAGCCCCCACCCCCCCCCCCACCCUCAUCGAAUGCUGCUUACUUUGUCAAAAGACUGGCUAUGACCAAGGUGAGGAUAUUUCUGGAAAACUGGGCAAAAAGGGAAAGCCCACAGUAUUCUUCCUUGGCAGUCAACCACAGGUUUACUUUACAAUGAUGUAUUAAAAACUUGCAGCUUGAAAAAUGGAAUGCAAAUAAAAGGUUCUCUUUGGGUUUGUCUUAAUGGAGUUAAACUGGAGCAGCCUAUAAAACAUUUUUAGGGUGAUGUCCUCUGGGUCCUUCUGUUCUGCACACCCACUCAGUCUUCUCUCCCAGCCCCUUGACUGCACACACCCCUCUUUGCCUGAAGAUCUCCUGACUUGUCGCCAGCCAUAGAGGCUCGAAAGCUCUGGUUGUGAAGCAUAACGCAAUGCAUAGACCUGUCAGCCAUAAAAAAAAAAAAAAAAAAAAAAAAGCGACUUGGAUAACUUGUAUGCCUUCUUUUGUAUCAAUGUACCAAUUGUAAAUAAUGCUGAUCAACCUUUGUAGAGAAUAGUUUAUACAGCAUAUUCUAUUAUUGCUGAUUCUCAGUGAACUCUUGUUUUAAAAAAGGAAAAAAAGAAAUUUUCUAUUUACACCUUAUAUUUUGUUAUGCUGUCGGCCCAUGGCACUUUAACAAAACUCUGUGGGUUUUACGUAGCUGGUCAGUCAUGGGGUAUAUUAAAUAACUGUUGUUGCACAGACAA